AUGGAAGCUGAUAUCCAGCUCAUGAGACUUAUCCAGGAAAUGCGGGCAGAGAUCCACAAACUGGAGAAAGAGAAUCAAGCCCUCCGGAUGAAACUCACUGCAAGUAGUCAGAGAGCCUCAGGCUCAGGGAGAGAAUCAGGAGACGAAAGGGAGGAGGAAGCGCCAGGACAAUCUCCAGCAACCCUUCAGGGUGCCGUUUCCACUGAUGCAGCACCAGCAGUGCAGGAACACCAAGGCAAUGUCAUGAUUGUUAGACGCUAUUCCAUUUCAUCAUCAGUUUGCUCAUCUGCUGUAAAUGAUCCCUGGAAAUCUGGGAAAAGUCACCCAAAGAGCGGAAUUCUAGAAGGUCAGAGAACACUGAAGUCAUUGGCAUGUUCUCCAAUUAAGAAGCAAGACAUGGAAGAAAAGGUGUUUGCCACAGAUUCUCUCACCAGCAAUAGGACCAGCCAAAGAGCUUCUCCUGAGCAUGUUUGUGGUUGCAGGGACAAGACAAAGGCAGUCAGUUUCCUGUUACCCAUGGACAUGUCUUCAUAUUCCAAAAAUUCAAGUUCUUUGAAACACUCACCAAAUCAGGCCACAAACCAGCUAAGUAUCAUUGCAGAAUAG